AGUUCCCAGCCUGGAGCCUAAGCAUACACUGCAUUAAUCAGACUUGCUGGAAUGAUCACAUGGUUUUCUAGCUGCCUCCCCUGUUAGCUGCCGCUUGUCAGCAGCUGGCGGAGCUGGAGGCUGCAGGCCCCUGUCUGCAGAAAGCCUUUUACUUCAGAAUAUUGGGGGGUGUGGAAACCCCGCCUCAUUUUUCUGCACUUUGCACCAUCUGACUAACUAAAUGGUUGUCCUCCAUACCAAAAAGACUACCACACAAUCUAAGGAAAUUGUCUCUGACUAGGUCAUGUUUGCAUUUGAAGAAUUCAGUGAACAGAGUAUCUGCCAAGCCCGGGCUUCCGUGAUGGUCUACGAUGACACCAGUAAGAAAUGGGUACCAAUCAAACCUGGCCAGCAGGGAUUCAGCCGGAUCAACAUCUACCACAACACUGCCAGCAACACCUUCAGAGUCGUUGGAGUCAAGUUGCAGGAUCAGCAGGUUGUGAUCAAUUAUUCAAUCGUGAAAGGGCUGAAGUACAAUCAGGCCACGCCAACCUUCCACCAGUGGCGAGAUGCCCGCCAGGUCUACGGCUUAAACUUUGCAAGUAAAGAAGAGGCAACCACGUUCUCCAAUGCAAUGCUGUUUGCCCUGAACAUCAUGAAUUCCCAAGAAGGAGGCCCCUCCAGCCAGCGUCAGGUGCAGAAUGGCCCCUCUCCUGAUGAGAUGGACAUCCAGAGAAGACAAGUGAUGGAGCAGCACCAGCAGCAGCGUCAGGAAUCUCUAGAAAGAAGAACCUCGGCCACAGGGCCCAUCCUCCCACCAGGACAUCCUUCAUCUGCAGCCAGCGCCCCCGUCUCAUGUAGUGGGCCUCCACCGCCCCCCCCACCCCCAGUCCCACCUCCACCCACUGGGGCUACCCCACCUCCCCCACCCCCACUGCCAGCCGGAGGAGCCCAGGGGUCCAGCCACGACGAGAGCUCCAUGUCAGGACUGGCCGCUGCCAUAGCUGGGGCCAAGCUGAGAAGAGUCCAACGGCCAGAAGACGCAUCUGGAGGCUCCAGUCCCAGUGGGACCUCAAAGUCCGAUGCCAACCGGGCAAGCAGCGGGGGUGGCGGAGGAGGCCUCAUGGAGGAAAUGAACAAACUGCUGGCCAAGAGGAGAAAAGCAGCCUCCCAGUCAGACAAGCCAGCCGAGAAGAAGGAAGAUGAAAGCCAAAUGGGCUACCUCGCCUUCCCAGGAGCCCCGGGGAGCACAGACCAGCCAGGGUCUCGGCGGGACUGGGACUCCAGGAGUACACUGCAGAGGGGCACGUCUGCCAGAAGCCCAGAGAGGCCACGGGAUAAUCACAGACAUCAAAAUACUGUGGCCUCGCUCCAGCCACAGCCCUGGGGAUCUGAAGACAUCGCUGGCCUUUCUUAGUCAGGUGCCAGUAUGUUGCAGUCCCAGCCCCUGAAAACUAAAACUCUCGCUCCUGGAGCUCUAAGAAGAAUGGAUUUCAAAGCCCAGGGGCUUCUGGAAGAGGAACAUUCUUGAAACCUUCAACCCCAAGGAUAGCACUCUCCUCCUCAGACCCCCAUCUUUUCUGUCUUGUUUUUCACAGGCCCCUGGCUACAGCUGGUUCUUGUUUGCCAUGGUCCCUUCUCAUACCCAGGACUAGCGUCUAAAGAGAGCAGGGCCUUCAGAAGAUCCACACACCACACAAGUGCAGUGGGAGGGAGAGAGGCUGAUGGCCGGCACUCGUUUUCUUGUUCAUGCUUCCUGGUAUUUCCCCAAUUCUCUGCAGUGAACAUGCACUAAGUUUAUCAUUAACAGAGAAGAAAGAAGGCUUAUUUGAAAGACGAAAAGAGCCCCAAAUGUGGAGUCCGGUGACUUGGGCAGGCCCUCUGCCAUGGCAGAGCUGGCCCUGGGCCAAUGGAGUUACUGCUCCGAGGACCAGUUCCACCACCUGAAAACCUGCACCCAGGCAUGGCCGCCUCACAGACUGUGCGACUGCCAGAGGUGGGGUGCAAGUCUCUGUGCCCAGGGCCUGGGAGUGCUGCGGCCACCUCUUUCCCAGCCUAGAGUCAAAGCAUAACUUCCCUUUUAAGCAGGGAGGGUUUUAAAAAAAUAACAUACAAGAAAAGAUGAUAAUUUUUUAGUGACUCUGAUGUCACCCUGUAUCGCUUUCAUCGUGGCCCCCACAUGUGUGUGUUGAUUGACAUAAUCUGUUAUUCAGCUGUCUUUAAAAUGAGGAGGCCUGAGAACCUCAUCCCAGCACCUGCAGGCUGGCACCUGCUUUUGCCUCUCGACCAGAGCCUCCCGGGACUUACUCGUUCACCACACAGAUACGCAGGGCGUUCCUGAUUCUCGUGUGGGGAUGUAGUGAGCAGAGGAGACAAAGCAAAGACCUCUGCCCACGGUGACAAGGGAGAGGUUCUUUGCUUCAGAUCAGAAUGACACAUCAGGUUGGGUGGCCGCCUGUCAACAGCUCAAAUGCUGUGCAUUCUGCUUCAUCAAGUGGAAGGAUUACUCUUAUUACUUAAUCAGUGGCAUGUUCCUGAUGCUGAAAAACCAUCCUGACGCACAUGCCAUGCAUGAUGAGUGUUAGGUGUCCCCACUGCUGGAUGAACACGUCCACUGUUCGAGCACUGCCACAGACCUAUUACACGGGCAGGUGUGUGUGCUGCACAGGGGGAGCAGGCCAGUCCACGGGGUGCUCAUGAGAAGUCAGUGAGAUGACAUACGGGAGGCAUCCGGCCCAAGGGGGGCUCAGGGCUUGCGGGUGUUGAGGGCCAGAAGGAAGUUCUAUAUCACCCUGCUGAGAGCCUGUAGCUCCCUGUAGCCUUCCCCUUCCCCAGCUUUGUCCACUGGCUCGAUUCUCUCCCCACUGAGAUUUUGCGUUUUCACUUUUAAAUAUUUAAUGUUUUGCUAAUUAUAAAAGUCAUAUGUGUUCAUUGGGAACAUUUGGAAAACUGAGGUUUUAUGAAGUGUCCAAUGAUGUCCUGCCCUGGCCCCAGGUGGCCUUCCUAAACAGACUCCCUUCUUCUCCA